AAAGCAAGAACAGCACUGCUGGGCUGGAGACGGCGGGAGCCGCUGCUCUCCGGCUGAGGGAAUCAGAGACAGCUCCGUCCCUAGUGGAGCGCAGGGGAGGCAGAAGUCAUGACAGGCGAGGUGGGUUCUGAGGUUCACCUAGAAAUCAAUGACCCAAACGUCAUUUCACAAGAGGAAGCAGAUAGUCCUUCAGAUAGUGGACAGGGCAGCUAUGAAACAAUUGGACCCUUGAGUGAAGGAGAUUCAGAUGAAGAGAUAUUUGUAAGUAAGAAGUUGAAAAACAGGAAGGUUCUACAAGACAGUGAUUCCGAAACAGAGGACACAAAUGCCUCUCCAGAGAAAACUACCUAUGACAGUGCCGAGGAGGAAAAUAAAGAGAAUUUAUAUGCUGGGAAAAAUACAAAAAUCAAAAGGAUUUACAAAACUGUGGCAGACAGUGAUGAAAGUUACAUGGAAAAGUCUUUGUAUCAGGAAAAUCUUGAAGCGCAAGUGAAACCUUGCUUAGAGCUGAGUCUUCAGUCUGGAAACUCUACAGACUUUACCACUGACAGAAAGAGUUCCAAAAAGCACAUACAUGAUAAAGAAGGAACUGCAGGAAAAGCAAAAGUAAAAUCAAAAAGAAGACUUGAGAAAGAGGAGAGAAAAAUGGAAAAAAUUAGACAGCUAAAAAAGAAGGAAACAAAAAACCAGGAAGAUGAUGUAGAACAGCCAUUUAAUGACAGUGGCUGUCUUCUUGUGGAUAAAGACCUUUUUGAAACUGGGUUGGAGGAUGAAAAUAACUCUCCAUUGGAAGAUGAAGAGUCAUUAGAAUCAAUAAGAGCAGCUGUAAAAAACAAAGUAAAAAAGCACAAGAAAAAAGAACCAUCUUUGGAGAGUGGGGUCCAUUCAUUUGAGGAAGGAAGUGAGUUAUCAAAAGGAACCACGAGGAAGGAAAGAAAGGCAGCCAGAUUAAGUAAAGAAGCAUUAAAACAACUGCAUAGUGAGACUCAGCGCCUUAUUCGAGAGUCUGCACUGAACCUUCCAUAUCAUAUGCCUGAGAAUAAAACCAUUCAUGAUUUCUUCAAACGUAAACCCCGGCCCACUUGCCACGGAAAUGCCAUGGCACUAUUGAAGUCAUCUAAAUAUCAGUCAAGCCAUCACAAAGAAAUCAUAGACACUGCAAAUACUACUGAAAUGAACAGUGAUCACCAUAGUAAAGGUUCUGAGCAGACAACAGGUGCAGAAAAUGAAGUGGAAACUAAUGCACUCCCUGUAGUUUCAAAGGAAACCCAGAUCAUUACUGGAUCAGAUGAGUCUUGCAGGAAGGAUUUGGUAAAAAAUGAAGAGCUAGAAAUUCAGGAGAAACAGAAGCAGAGUGACAUUAGACCUUCACCUGGGGACAGCUCAGUGUUGCAACAGGAAUCCAACUUCCUCGGGAACAAUCACAGUGAGGAAUGUCAGGUUGGAGGGCUUGUAGCAUUUGAACCUCAUGCCCUGGAGGGUGAAGGCCCCCAAAAUCCAGAAGAAACAGAUGAGAAAGUGGAAGAGCCUGAGCAGCAAAAUAAAUCAUCAGCAGUUGGGCCACCUGAAAAAGUGAGACGGUUUACUCUGGAUAGACUUAAGCAACUGGGAGUAGAUGUUUCCAUUAAACCACGGCUAGGUGCUGAUGAAGAUUCCUUUGUGAUACUUGAACCUGAAACCAACAGAGAACUGGAAGCCUUGAAGCAGCGUUUCUGGAAGCAUGCUAAUCCAGCAGCCAAACCCAGGGCUGGUCAGACAGUGAAUGUGAACGUCAUAGUGAAAGACAUGGGCACUGAUGGAAAGGAAGAGCUAAAAGCAGAUGUGGUACCUGUGACUUUAGCACCUAAGAAGUUGGAUGGAGCAAGCCACACAAAACCAGGUGAAAAGCUUCAGGUGUUAAAAGCUAAACUGCAAGAAGCAAUGAAACUCCGAAGGUUUGAGGAGCGCCAGAAGCGCCAAGCACUGUUUAAAUUAGAUAAUGAAGAUGGGUUUGAGGAAGAGGAGGAGGAAGAGGAAGAAAUGACAGAUGAGUCUGAGGAAGAUGGAGAAGAGAAGGUAGAGAAAGAAGAGAAAGAGGAAGAACUAGAGGAAGAGGAGGAGAAAGAAGAGGAGGAGGAAGAAGAAGGAAAUCAGGAGACUGCAGAAUUCCUUCUUAGUAGUGAAGAAAUAGAAACAAAAGAUGAAAAAGAAAUGGAUAAAGAAAAUAAUGAUGGCAGUAGUGAAAUUGGCAAGGCAGUUGGCUUCCUCUCUGUUCCCAAGUCUCUCUCAUCAGAUUCUACUUUACUUCUGUUUAAGGACAGCUCUUCCAAGAUGGGUUACUUUCCUACUGAAGAAAAAUCAGAAACAGAUGAAAACUCAGGCAAGCAGCCUAGCAAACUGGAUGAGGAUGAUUCAUGUUCAUUGCUAACAAAGGAGAGCAGCCACAAUAGCAGCUUUGAGCUGAUUGGCUCCACGAUUCCAUCCUAUCAGCCUUGCAACAGACAAACAGGCCGUGGGACCAGUUUUUUCCCUACAGCAGGAGGAUUCAGAUCUCCUUCCCCUGGGCUAUUUCGAGCCAGUUUGGUCAGCUCAGCUUCUAAGAGUUCAGGGAAACUGUCUGAGCCUUCACUUCCCAUAGAGGAUUCCCAGGAUCUGUAUAACGCCUCCCCAGAGCCUAAGACACUUUUCCUAGGAGCAGGAGACUUCCAGUUCUGUUUAGAAGAUGACACUCAGAGCCAACUGUUGGAUGCAGAUGGGUUCUUAAAUGUUAGAAACCACAGGAAUCAGUACCAAGCUUUGAAGCCUCGAUUGCCAUUGGCCAGUAUGGAUGAGAAUGCCAUGGAUGCCAACAUGGAUGAGCUGUUGGAUUUGUGUACUGGAAAGUUCACAUCUCAGGCUGAAAAACAUCUACCCAGGAAGAGUGACAAGAAAGAGAACAUGGAGGAACUUCUGAACCUUUGUUCAGGAAAAUUCACUUCUCAGGAUGCCUCCACUCCAGCCUCAUCAGAGUUAAAUAAACAGGAGAAGGAGAGCAGCAUGGGUGAUCCAAUGGAAGAAGCACUUGCUCUUUGCUCAGGCUCUUUUCCCACAGACAAGGAAGAGGAAGACGAGGAGGAGGAAUUUGGAGACUUUCGGCUUGUUUCAAAUGAUAAUGAGUUUGAUAGUGAUGAGGAUGAACACAGUGACUCUGGUAAUGAUCUGGCACUGGAAGACCAUGAAGAUGAUGAUGAAGAAGAACUCCUGAAGCGAUCUGAGAAGUUGAAAAGGCAAAUGAGGUUGAGGAAAUACCUGGAGGAUGAGGCAGAGGUGUCAGGAAGUGAUGUGGGAAGCGAAGAUGAGUAUGAUGGGGAAGAAAUUGAUGAAUAUGAAGAGGACGUAAUUGAUGAAGUACUUCCUUCUGAUGAGGAACUGCAGAGUCAAAUCAAGAAAAUACACAUGAAAACUAUGUUGGAUGAUGAUAAGCGACAGCUACGUUUAUACCAAGAGAGGUACCUUGCUGAUGGGGAUCUGCACAGCGAUGGUCCUGGGCGAAUGAGGAAGUUUCGAUGGAAAAACAUAGAUGAUGCUUCCCAGAUGGACUUGUUCCACAGAGACUCUGAUGAUGAUCAGACUGAAGAACAGCUUGAUGAGUCAGAAGCCAGGUGGAGGAAGGAGCGAAUUGAACGAGAGCAGUGGCUUCGGGACAUGGCACAGCAGGGGAAAAUUACAGCUGAAGAAGAAGAAGAAAUUGGGGAGGACAGUCAGUUUAUGAUACUGGCCAAGAAAGUUACAGCCAAAGCACUGCAGAAGAAUGCCAGUCGCCCUAUGGUUAUUCAGGAAUCAAAGUCUUUGCUCAGAAAUCCUUUUGAAGCCAUCAGACCAGGAAGUGCUCAACAGGUGAAGACAGGCUCACUGCUAAACCAGCCCAAAGCUGUGCUUCAGAAACUGGCUGCUCUCUCUGACCAUAACCCCAGUGCUCCUCGAAAUUCAAGAAACUUUGUCUUUCAUACACUUUCUCCUGUCAAGGCUGAGGCGGCAAAGGAAUCGUCUAAGUCUCAGGUAAAGAAAAGGGGUCCAUCUUUCAUGACUUCUCCUUCACCUAAGCACCUCAAAACAGAUGAUAGCACUUCAGGAUUGACGCGAAGCAUCUUCAAAUAUUUGGAGAGCUAACACCAUCAAAGGUGCCAAAAUCUACAUUGAGACUGCUUUGAGAAGUUUCUAGCACUGAAAGUUGGAAUUGACACUCCAGCCAAUGAUCCUUCCUUCUUUCAUAAUCAAUGCAAUAAGAUUGCAGACAGAAAUUCCAGUGAUUUCUACUGCACAGCUCUGGACAUCUCUUUUCCUAGUAUUAUUCCCUGAAUUGGCCACUGAUUUCAAUUCUGCAGUAUUUACAACAUCAACAACUCAUGGAAUACUUGGGUGAGGUUUCCUUUUUUUUUUUUUUUUUAAGAUGGGAGUCUCACUCUGUUGCCCAGCUUGGAGUGCAGUGGCGUGAUCUCGGCUCACCACAAUCUCUGCCUCCCAGGUUCAAGCGAUUCUCCUCCUUCAGCCUCCCGAGUAGCUGGGAUUACAGGCAUGUGCCAAUACGCCCAGCUAAUUUUUGUAUUUUUAGUAGAGACGGGGUUUCACCAUGUUGGCCAGGCUGGUCUUGAACUCCUGACCUCAAAUGAUCCAUCCACCUCGGCCCCACAAAGUGCUGGUCACAUGCAUGAGUCACUGCACCUGGCCUUGGGUUAGGUUUCACUUCCUCCAUUAGACAUUUGACAUUUUAUUGUAGCAGCUUUCUGGGUUAAUAUCUCUUUGUGAUUGAUAGAAGUGGUUGGAAGAGGAAGAGUAGGGAAAAGUGUGACAUUACAGAUUAAACAGUGAAAAUCAGUACCAUAAUGACUCCUUUACACCCAUGAGAUACGUACCAUGAUGACCAGGGCUCGGUGAAAGAAAGAUUUCUUUUUUUUUUUUUGAGAUAGUCUCACUUUGUUGCCCAGUCUGGAGUGCAGUGGCGCAAUCUCGGCUCACGGCAACCUCUGCCUCCCGGGUUCAAGUGAUUCUCCUGUCUCAGCCUCCCAAGUAGCUGGGACUACAGGUGCAUGCCACCACACCUGGCUAAUUUUUGUAUUUUUAGUGGAGACAGGGAGUCACCAUGUUGGCCAGGCUGGUCUCGAUCUCCUGACCUCAAGUGAUCCAGCUGCCUCAGCCUCCCAAAGUGCUGAGAUUACAGGCGUGAGCCACUGUGCCCAGCCAAAAGAACGAUUUCUUAGAUGGAGGACCUAGGAACCAACAGAUGGGCUGCUGUAUUACUCUUACCCCUUUCAUUUUCCUGUAUGCUUCUUCCCAAGGCAGCAUCAAAUUUUGAAUUAAUUUUUGCUGCUUAAUAAGGACUUAAACUGGUACCCAAGUCAGAAAGACUCUGCCUCUAAUUUUCUGGGGCUUGGGGAUGAAGAUAAAGUGUUACACCCAGUGUUUGUCCACCACAGUCUGUGGGGCAGAGAGACCCUUCCUGGGACUGAAUUCUCAAUUUGAAGCACUGUUGUUCAAAGAUCUCCCUUCUGGGUCUGACAAGAAGAAACAUAACCCUUAUUUAUUGCAUUCUUCUGGCUUACAUACAUUGCCCUCACUAAUCAAUGGACAUUUCAGCAUUUCAUUACUAAUUUUGAGAGAAGGCCACCAUGGAAUUUAAUAAAAAUAUUAUUGAAGAGAAUUGCCAUCAUUCUCCAUUUUCCCUGAACUACCACAAGCUUCUCAGAAUUUUAGACAAAUGUUUUUCCCCUCAGAACUGAGCAUCAGUGCUGCUUUGGAAAAACAUUCCAUGUGAAUACUGUGGUUUCAGUGUCAGGACCUGUACUUGGGCAGUUGGAAGAGAGUGUGCCAGUUUUUUACUGGGAGAUGGGAACACCAAUUUAAUUGAUGCAAUUAGGUUGUAGGUUUUUUACAGUUUUUCUUUUCUUUUCUUUUUCUUUUUCUUUUCUUUUCUUUUCUUUUUUUUUUUUUGAGACAUAGGCUGGCUCUGUCACCUAGGCUGGAAUACAAUGGCAUGAUCUCGGCUUACUGCAACCUCCGCCUCCUAGGUUCAAGCAAUUCUGCCUCGGCCUCCCAAAUAGCAGGGAUUACAGGCACCUGCCACCACUCCCAGCUAAUUUUUUGUAUUUUUAUUAGAGAUGAGGUUUCGCCAUGUUGGCCAGGCUGGUCUUGAACUCCUGACCUGAGGUGAUCCACCCGUCUCGGCCUCCCAAAGUGCUGGGAUUAUAGGCAUGAGCCACCGCACCCGGCCGGUUUUCUACAGUUUUCUAAUACUCAAGAUGUUGACUUUGACAAUACUUAUGUUUGUAUACUUGUAAUCUUAUAAUGGGGAAAAUGUGUAUAAAGAUGUUUUAAUAUGUAUGUAGUUUUUCAAUAAAUCUUAAUGCCUUGAAGGGAAGAUUUGCUGUCCAGCUUGAAUGCUCAUUCUUGGGUCAGUGCCUGUCUAACCUUGAGGAGCAUUUCAUUUUCAGGUUAUCUCCAUCCCAGGGAAACCCUCUGGGUCUAAACUGAGAAGCUGCUGCAAUUGUCCCCUCACUGGCUUCUCAGUCCUAGUGAAUUGAUCAAGUUAACUUACCAAGUGGUUUGGGUUCAGCUCAGGUGAAGAGGAUAAUUGAGUUUACAUAAAUGGUACCUUCUAUUAUAGCUCUUUGUUUAAAAAACUUAUUUUUUAGAGACAGUCUCAUUCUGUUGCCCAGGUUAGAGUGCAGUGGCACAAUCAUAGCUCACUGUACCCUUGAACUCCUGGGCUUCAGCAUCCUCCUUCCUCAACCUUUGGAAUAGCUGGGCCACAUUACAGGCAUAUGCCACCAUGCCCAGCUAAUUAUUUUAUUUUAGUAGAGACAGGGUCUUGCUGUGUUGCCCCAGCUGAUCUUGAACUCCUGGCCUCAAGUAAUCCUCCCACCUUGGCCUCCCAAAAUGCUGGGGUCACAGGCUCAGCCACCAUGCCCAGCCUGUUACAGCUUUGAUUGGCCUUUCUCUUUAGCUAAGUUUGUAUGUACUUCAUUUUAUCCAUGGGUUCAAGAUACAUGUUUUUGCCUCUUUCUUUGAACUCUCUAAACAGUUCCCAAGGCAAAGUAGCCCUUGCUGGGCAAAAGAGAACUGAGCAGGAAGGCUAGAUAUUUCUUCCCUCUUGUUUCCCUACAUGUCUUUUGAGGAGAGAUAGAAAAGACAAUUGGAAUUGACAACUGAGGAUAAGAAAAUUCAGCCAGGUCCGGUGGCUCACGCCAGCACUUUAGGAGACUGAGGUGGGUGCAUUGCUUGAACUCAGGAGUUCGAGACCAGCCUGGGAAACAUGGUGAAAUCCCAACUCUAAAAAAAAAAAAAAAAAGAAAAAAAAAAGAAAAUUAGUGCCUGAGAAAUCCAGGGAGAAAAUGGUUUCUGGGCUGGGCGUGGUGGCUUAUGCCUGUAAUCUCAGCACUUUGGGAGGCUGAGGCAGCUGGAUCACCUAAGGUCAGGAGUUGGAGACCAGACUGACCAACAAGGUGAAACCCCGUCUCUACUAAAAAUACAAAAAUCAGCCAGGCUUGGUGGUGGCAGGUGCCUGUAGUCCCAGCUACUUGGGAGGCUGAGACAAGAGAAUUGCUUGAACCUGGGAGGCAGAGGUUGCAGUGAGCCGAGAUCACGCCACUGCUCUCCAGCAUGGGCGACAGAGUGAGACUCCCUCUCAAAAAAAAAAAGAAAGAAAGAAAAUGGUUUCUGAUUGAGGCUCCUGGGAGAAAGCACUCUUUGGAGAAAGAAAACUUGAGUCAAACUCUGGGUUACUUUUCCUUAUGCCAGGAUGGCUGCUAUAAAGUAAGCUAAGCCUUGAUCUUGGUAACAGGAUUGACAUGGACAGUUUCAAUCUGACCCAUAUGCCCUUUGCCCAAAGCACUGAGCCAGCAGCAUCAGUUAUGUUUUAAUGAAAUUGAAGCCCCAGGACCUGCCACUAUGGCUCUGAGGAGGACUCAGCUUCACUAGCUUGGAAAUUACAUAUUUGGAGGGAUGAGAGCCCAUGAGUGUGGGAGAUAGGGUAGGCUCAGUGUCAGUGUUUUUGUUUCUUCCUUGUUCCAUACACUUGAGUAGGGAUACAUGGUAUUAACCUCUUUAAACAGGUCUCUAAUUUCAUCUCAUUAAUUCACAGUUGCACAGCCAUACUAGGGUCUCUUCCAUAAACCAUAAGAUUUUAUUCACCAAAGCUCUAGAGACAAGGUACUCAGAUCUCUGUGGCAUCCCUCAUUUUCUCAACUGCUUCUCUACAAACUUCUCCUCACUUUGAGAGUUUCUAAUGCUCAGGCUGGGAGACUUUUUAGGGGGUGUUUUUGGUUUUUAUCUCCUAGGGUUAUGUCUAAUCACUCUUGUGGCAUCCUGUCCUGGGAUUUGUGCUCCUAAGGAUAGAGGAGAGUAUUUCUGGGAGGAGUGUUCCCAUGAUACUAUUUGAUUAUGUCAUCCUUGAGAUGGUAUUGUAUCUUCUACCCUUAUAUCCUACUCAUCGCCUGGCACACAGCUUGGAAUGUAGUGGUGCCUACCACAGUUUGAAUAAAUAACACUACACCUUUCA